AUGCGGAGCGGCUAGGUGGUGCACGGGAAACGCGGGCGUAGGUGACCGGCGGCUUUCUCAGUUUUGGUGGAGACGGGCGCAUGUGGGCGCUUUGCUCGCUGCUGCGGUCCGCGGCCGGACGCACCAUGUCGCAGGGACGCACCAUAUCGCAGGCACCCGCCCGCCGCGAGCGGCCGCGCAAGGACCCGCUGCGGCACCUGCGCACGCGAGAGAAGCGCGGACCGUCGGGGUGCUCCGGCGGCCCAAACACCGUGUACCUGCAGGUGGUGGCAGCGGGUAGCCGGGACUCGGGCGCCGCGCUCUACGUCUUCUCCGAGUUCAACCGGUAUCUCUUCAACUGUGGAGAAGGCGUUCAGAGACUCAUGCAGGAGCACAAGUUAAAGGUUGCUCGCCUGGACAACAUAUUCCUGACACGAAUGCACUGGUCUAAUGUUGGGGGCUUAAGUGGAAUGAUUCUUACUUUAAAGGAAACCGGGCUUCCAAAGUGUGUACUUUCUGGACCUCCACAACUGGAAAAAUACCUCGAAGCAAUCAAAAUAUUUUCUGGUCCAUUGAAAGGAAUAGAACUGGCUGUGCGGCCCCACUCUGCCCCAGAAUACGAGGAUGAAACCAUGACAGUUUACCAGAUCCCCAUACACAGUGAACAGAGGAGGGGAAAGCACCAACCAUGGCAGAGUCCAGAAAGGCCUCUCAGCAGGCUCAGUCCAGAGCGAUCUUCAGACUCCGAGUCGAAUGAAAAUGAGCCACACCUUCCACAUGGUGUUAGCCAGAGAAGAGGGGUCAGGGACUCUUCCCUGGUCGUAGCUUUCAUCUGUAAGCUUCACUUAAAGAGAGGAAACUUCUUGGUGCUCAAAGCAAAGGAGAUGGGCCUCCCAGUUGGGACAGCUGCCAUCGCUCCCAUCAUUGCUGCUGUCAAGGACGGGAAAAGCAUCACUCAUGAAGGAAGAGAGAUUUUGGCUGAAGAGCUGUGUACUCCUCCAGAUCCUGGUGCUGCUUUUGUGGUGGUAGAAUGUCCAGAUGAAAGCUUCAUUCAACCCAUCUGUGAGAAUGCCACCUUUCAGAGGUACCAAGGAAAGGCAGAUGCCCCCGUGGCCUUGGUGGUUCACAUGGCCCCAGCAUCUGUGCUUGUGGACAGCAGGUACCAGCAGUGGAUGGAGAGGUUUGGGCCUGACACCCAGCACUUGGUCCUGAAUGAGAACUGUGCCUCAGUUCACAACCUUCGCAGCCACAAGAUUCAAACCCAGCUCAACCUCAUCCACCCGGACAUCUUCCCCCUGCUCACCAGUUUCCGCUGUAAGAAGGAGGGCCCCACCCUCAGUGUGCCCAUGGUUCAGGGUGAAUGCCUCCUCAAGUACCAGCUCCGUCCCAGGAGGGAGUGGCAGAGGGAUGCCAUUAUUACUUGCAAUCCUGAGGAAUUCAUAGUUGAGGCGCUGCAGCUUCCCAACUUCCAGCAGAGCGUGCAGGAGUACAGGAGGAGUGCGCAGGACGGCCCAGCCCCAGCAGAGAAAAGAAGUCAGUACCCAGAAAUCAUCUUCCUUGGAACAGGGUCUGCCAUCCCGAUGAAGAUUCGAAAUGUCAGUGCCACACUUGUCAACAUAAGCCCCGACACGUCUCUGCUACUGGACUGUGGUGAGGGCACAUUUGGGCAGCUGUGCCGUCAUUACGGAGACCAGGUGGACAGGGUCCUGGGCACCCUGGCUGCUGUGUUUGUGUCCCACCUGCACGCAGAUCACCACACGGGCUUGCCAAGUAUCUUGCUGCAGAGAGAACGCGCCUUGGCAUCUUUGGGAAAGCCGCUUCACCCUUUGCUGGUGGUUGCCCCCAACCAGCUCAAAGCCUGGCUCCAGCAGUACCACAACCAGUGCCAGGAGGUCCUGCACCACAUCAGUAUGAUUCCUGCCAAAUGCCUUCAGGAAGGGGCUGAGAUCUCCAGUCCUGCAGUGGAAAGAUUGAUCAGUUCGCUGUUGCGAACAUGUGAUUUGGAAGAGUUUCAGACCUGUCUGGUGCGGCACUGCAAGCAUGCGUUUGGCUGUGCGCUGGUGCACACCUCUGGCUGGAAAGUGGUCUAUUCCGGGGACACCAUGCCCUGCGAGGCUCUGGUCCGGAUGGGGAAAGAUGCCACCCUCCUGAUACAUGAAGCCACCCUGGAAGAUGGUUUGGAAGAGGAAGCAGUGGAAAAGACACACAGCACAACGUCCCAAGCCAUCAGCGUGGGGAUGCGGAUGAACGCGGAGUUCAUUAUGCUGAACCACUUCAGCCAGCGCUAUGCCAAGGUCCCCCUCUUCAGCCCCAACUUCAGCGAGAAAGUGGGAGUUGCCUUUGACCACAUGAAGGUCUGCUUUGGAGACUUUCCAACAAUGCCCAAGCUGAUUCCCCCACUGAAAGCCCUGUUUGCUGGCGACAUCGAGGAGAUGGAGGAGCGCAGGGAGAAGCGGGAGCUGCGGCAGGUGCGGGCGGCCCUCCUGUCCAGGGAGCUGGCAGGCGGCCUGGAGGAUGGGGAGCCUCAGCAGAAGCGGGCCCACACAGAGGAGCCACAGGCCAAGAAGGUCAGAGCCCAGUGAAGAUCUGGGAGACCCUGAACUCAGAAGGCUGUGUGUCUUCUGCCCCACGCACGCACCCGUAUCUGCCCUCCUUGCUGGUAGAAGCUGAAGAGCACGGUCCCCCAGGAGGCAGCUCAGGAUAGGUGGUAUGGAGCUGUGCCGAGGCUUGGGCUCCCACAUAAGCACUAGUCUAUAGAUGCCUCUUAGGACUGGUGCCUGGCACAGCCGCGGGCCAGGAGGCUGCCACACGGAAGCAAGCAGAUGAACUAAUUUCAUUUCAAGGCAGUUUUUAAAGAAGUCUUGGAAACAGACGGCGGCACCUUUCCUCUAAUCCAGCAAAGUGAUUCCCUGCACACCAGAGACAAGCAGAGUAACAGGAUCAGUGGGUCUAAGUGUCCGAGACUUAACGAAAAUAGUAUUUCAGCUGCAAUAAAGAUUGAGUUUGCAAUUGUGAGUUCUUUUGCUUCCUCCUGCUGCUGCUACAGAGCAGGGUCUGCUGUGCACCACCUUGGAGAAGGCUCUCUGUGCUGUAGUGUGGCAGCUGCCUGGUACCCGGGUGGCUUGGAAGAAGUCAGCUCCCGUCGUAGUGAGCACCUCUGGAACCUGUCCUCAGAGAGCCACCCUUAUUCGCCAAGUCUUUUUGACAACUCGAGCUGUGCCAGCUCACAGCAGGGCGUGCUUUCUCUAUCAAUCAAUCAAUCAAUCAAUCAAAUCAAUCAGUGAGAGCCUGGCUGGGCUGGUGUCAUUGGUCAGGGAAAUGCAAGUCUUCUGGUGGUUCUGGGUAAAAGUGGAGACAAUAGAUUUGCUGUGUUGUUGCUUCCAUACUGAGAGGAGUGAGGAUCACUUUGCCCUCGAAGGUUUUGAGAAAUGGCACACGGGGCUGGUUUCCAUUGUCCUCCUUGCGGGAUUUACAGACGUGGAUUAGUGCUCGACAAAUGGAGAGCAUUUUCCAAGGAAGUAAGUAAGUAAAGUAAGUAAGUAAGUAAGUAAGUUGAAUCUAGUAUUUAUUGUGUAUAUUCCCUACCCAGGAGAAUGUAAAAAGAAGAGCUUUAAAAACUCAAAAGACAAGCAAGCGAGAGAUCAGCCAGGGACCUGGCUUUACACAGGUGGUGACCUUCAGGCUCCAUCCCGGUGUGCAUUUGAGAUUGACGGCCAUGUCCCCGCAGGUUUAUUAAAGCAAGAACAGAUGCCAAGCUCAGGGAUAAUAAAUCUAUUUUAAUAACGUUA